CCUUCAGUCUCAGCCGCCAACUCCGGAGGCGCGGUGCUCGGCCCGGGAGCGCGAGCGGGAGGAGCAGAGACCCGCAGCCGGGAGCCCGAGCGCGGGCGAUGCAGGCUCCGCGAGCGGCACCUGCGGCUCCUCUAAGCUACGACCGUCGUCUCCGCGGCAGCAGCGCGGGCCCCAGCAGCCUCGGCAGCCACAGCCGCUGCAGCCGGGGCAGCCUCCGCUGCUGUCGCCUCCUCUGAUGCGCUUGCCCUCUCCCGGCCCCGGGACUCCGGGAGAAUGUGGGUCCUAGGCAUCGCGGCAACUUUUUGCGGAUUGUUCUUGCUUCCAGGUGAGAAUACCCAGAGGCCAGCAGCCGAGGCCAGGCUUUGCGCUGCAAAUCCAGUGCUACCAGUGUGAAGAAUUCCAGCUGAACAACGACUGCUCCUCCCCCGAGUUCAUUGUGAAUUGCACGGUGAACGUUCAAGACAUGUGUCAGAAAGAAGUGAUGGAGCAAAGUGCCGGGAUCAUGUACCGCAAGUCCUGUGCAUCAUCAGCGGCCUGUCUCAUCGCCUCUGCCGGGUACCAGUCCUUCUGCUCCCCAGGGAAACUGAACUCAGUUUGCAUCAGCUGCUGCAACACCCCUCUUUGUAACGGGCCAAGGCCCAAGAAAAGGGGAAGUUCUGCCUCGGCCCUCAGGCCAGGGCUCCGCACCACCAUCCUGUUCCUCAAAUUAGCCCUCUUCUCGGCACACUGCUGAAGCUGAAGGAGAUGCCACCCCCUCCUGCAUUGUUCUUCCAGCCCUCGCCCCCAACCCCCCACCUCCCUGAGUGAGUUUCUUCUGGGUGUCCUUUUAUUCUGGGUAGGGAGCGGGAGUCCGUGUUCUCUUUUGUUCCUGUGCAAAUAAUGAAAGAGCUCGGUAAAGCAUUCUGAAUAAAUUCAGCCUGACUGAAUUUUCAGUAUGUACUUGAAGGAAGGAGGUGGAGUGAAAGUUCACCCCCAUGUCUGUGUAACCGGAGUCAAGGCCAGGCUGGCAGAGUCAGUCCUUAGAAGUCACUGAGGUGGGCAUCUGCCUUUUGUAAAGCCUCCAGUGUCCAUUCCAUCCCUGAUGGGGGCAUAGUUUGAGACUGCAGAGUGAGAGUGACGUUUUCUUAGGGCUGGAGGGCCAGUUCCCACUCAAGGCUCCCUCGCUUGACAUUCAAACUUCAUGCUCCUGAAAACCAUUCUCUGCAGCAGAAUUGGCUGGUUUCGCGCCUGAGUUGGGCUCUAGUGACUCGAGACUCAAUGACUGGGACUUAGACUGGGGCUCGGCCUCGCUCUGAAAAGUGCUUAAGAAAAUCUUCUCAGUUCUCCUUGCAGAGGACUGGCGCCGGGACGCGAAGAGCAACGGGCGCUGCACAAAGCGGGCGCUGUCGGUGGUGGAGUGCGCAUGUACGCGCAGGCGCUUCUCGUGGUUGGCGUGCUGCAGCGACAGGCGGCAGCACAGCACCUGCACGAACACCCGCCGAAACUGCUGCGAGGACACCGUGUACAGGAGCGGGUUGAUGACCGAGCUGAGGUAGAAAAACGUCUCCGAGAAGGGGAGGAGGAUCAUGUACGCCCGGAAGUAGGACCUCGUCCAGUCGUGCUUGGGUUUGGCCGCAGCCAUGAUCCUCCGAAUCUGGUUGGGCAUCCAGCAUACGGCCAAUGUCACAACAAUCAGCCCUGGGCAGACACGAGCAGGAGGGAGAGACAGAGAAAAGAAAAACACAGCAUGAGAACACAGUAAAUGAAUAAAACCAUAAAAUAUUUAGCCCCUCUGUUCUGUGCUUACUGGCCAGGAAAUGGUACCAAUUUUUCAGUGUUGGACUUGACAGCUUCUUUUGCCACAAGCAAGAGAGAAUUUAACACUGUUUCAAACCCGGGGGAGUUGGCUGUGUUAAAGAAAGACCAUUAAAUGCUUUAGACAGUGUAUUUAUACCAGUUGAUGUCUGUUAAUUUUAAAAAAAUGUUUUCAUUGGUGUUUGUUUGCGUAUCCAGAAAGCAGUUCAUGUUAUCCAUAAAUCUGGUUUUGUCUUUUUUUGUUUUAAAGAAAAAGAUGUAUACAUACAGUAUAGCUGCAUUAGAUAAAGCAGUGUUUGUAUUUUAAAGGAUGUCUGCACAAAGAAGACCUAGUGAUAUUUUUAAAUCAAAUGGAAGAAGUGUCCCUUUGGCAACAAAGCAGCAUAUUUAAUGACACUGGUUUUGCAUUCAGUUUCAGGGGAAGCAAAGUCAGGAAUAGCCUGUCGCCAAGAAUGUUUUUUGGACAUAUACAUACUAGGUAUGCACACCUAUAAUCAUGAUGCUCAUAUCUGCAACAGCAUAUGUGUUUCUUUUCAGACACUUUUAGAUCCCUCAUGUGGGGAAAAAGAAUUAUUCAGAGAUGGCAAAUAUAAAACUUCCUUCUAGUUCAGCCAGUAACAUGUUCCCUUCCUUUGCAGCACUGAGCUGUGCUGUCAACAGCCCAGAAGCAAUCAGGCCCUAGAGAAGAGACCACUCAAAGGCCCUUCUGUAGAUCAAAUGUUUACUGCAUGUACAUUUGUUUGCAUGCCCACAUAUUUGUAUUCCAACUUAAGUAACCACCACCAGUUCUGCAAUUCUGACUGACAGAGAUAAAGAUGCUACAUAGACCACAAACAACUGAAAUCACAGGUAUCAUGAGAGUUUAGUUACAGUGACAAAAGCAAAAAAGAACAAAGGAAGAUCAGGGGAUCUGUGAAGCAUUUGCUCUCUCUUUUCGUAAGGAGCCAAGACACCCACAGUAAAUUCCCCUGUAGAGAGCUGCUACCUUAAAGCAGGAUUUGCAUUUUCAGAAAUGCUUCCUUCCUCUCCUACAUUUCAAUCGUAGUAAGAAACAUUUACUCACAUUUUCAAUCUUCUGAUUUUCUAGAAACCCUAGGGAAGUGACAGUUGGCAAUGAAUGCUUCCUGCCUAUGACCCAUGGUAAAUAUUCUAUUAAUAAAUGGGGGCCAGACAUGGUGGCGCAUGCCUGAUAUCUCAAUACUCUGGGAGGCCAAGGCAGAAGGAUCACUUAAGCCUAGAAAUUUGAGACCCACCUAGGCAACAUAGCAAGACCCCAUCUCUACAAAAAAAGAAAAACUUAGCCAGGCAUGGUGGUACAUACACACCUGUGGUCUCAGAUACUUUUUGGGGGCUGAGGCGGGAGGAUCACUUGAGCCCAGGAGGUGAAGGCUACAGUGAGACACGAAUGUGCCACUGCACUCCAGCCUGGCUGACAGAGUGAAACUGUCUCAAUAAACCAAUAAAUAAAUGCUCCAGGAAAAAACAGCCACAUUCACACAUCCAGAAUUGAGCCUCCUGUAUGCACUGGCCUGAGUAUUCCUUGCCUGCUGUUGGAGGGGACCCUAGCUGUGUUCAAAUCCUCCACAAAUCCAUAUGUGAGCAAGGAAGGCCUUGGAAACUCUUCUCCUUUGUUAAUUUCCACAGGUUUCUCCUGUCAACUCCCAGCCUAAAACUUUGAAAUAUAAGCCAAUUUGUUUA